GGCAGUCCUAGUACACAAGACACGUACUUGCCAUCACUAAAACAUUGCCUACCCACAUGAUGCCCUCUCUCCACAAAAUUGAUCCCUGGUGAGGAGUAACUAUUGACCGCCCACUGAGUGGUGACUCCUUAUGCUAAGCACCACGAAUACAAGGGCAGGAGCAGGAUUUUUGGUUGCACAGCCGGUGUUUCAGGCACCCAUCCUCCCAGGGAACCCAAGAGAAGAGCCCUGUAUCUCCUUAGUAAAUGCAGAACCCAAGCUCCCAAGCCAUUUUCCCCAGGCCAUCCUAAUGGCUCCCUCAGCCUUGAUGGGAGAAGCCACGAUGUUCCCACCCAUCGCCUUUUAGUAGCCACAAGAACCUGCCCGCCCACCCACUGCACGCCCAUUGGUUGGACAGUGGUAGAGGCGGGCCCUGACGAGCGCAUGCUCAGAGGGAGAAGUCAGCGGAGAAGCUGGGAGCUCCUUUGGAGGCUGCGGUGUCCCUGACUCUCCUGAGGGGGGCUCACUAACGGGUGGGUCCCAUGCCACAGUGUCUGAGGAGAAGCAGGAAGUGAGUCCCUGAGGAGACGCCGUGACCUGAGGGCUUCCCUUACUGAGGAGGCCUCGUGCUUCAUCUGCCACAAGCGGUGCCCAGGCCGGUGGUGACAACUGGGACGAUGCUCAGGCUUCUGAGACUUGCUUUGGCCUUCUACGGGAGGACGGCCGACCCUGCAGAGCGACAGGGCCCACAGCAGCAGGGCCUCCCACAAGGUGACACCCAGUUGACAACUGUGCAGGGAGUUGUCACAAGUUUCUGUGGUGAUUAUGGCAUGAUUGAUGAGUCGAUCUACUUCAGUAGUGAUGUUGUGACUGGCAACGUGCCUCUAAAAGUUGGACAAAAAGUUAAUGUGGUUGUGGAAGAAGAUAAACCACAUUAUGGAUUGAGAGCAAUCAAGGUGGAUGUUGUGCCUCGCCAUCUUUAUGGUGCUGGACCCUCAGACUCAGGAACCAGAGUUUUAAUUGGAUGUGUUACUUCUAUAAAUGAAGAUAAUAUUUAUAUUAGUAACAGCAUUUAUUUUUCCAUAGCCAUUGUUUCUGAAGAUUUUGUGCCUUAUAAGGGUGACUUGUUAGAAGUUGAAUAUUCCACUGAGCCAGGCAUCUCAAACAUCAAGGCAACUUCUGUGAAGCCCAUCCGUUGUAUUCAUACGGAAGAGGUCUGCAUUACUAGCGUACAUGGAAGAAAUGGGGUGAUAGAUUAUACUAUUUUUUUCACCUUGGAUUCUGUGAAACUUCCUGAUGGAUACGUACCUCAAGUAGAUGAUAUCGUCAAUGUGGUCAUGGUGGAGAGCAUUCAGUUCUGCUUUAUUUGGAGAGCGAUUUCUAUCACCCCAGUGCAUAAAUCGUAAUGACAAAGCAUUUUUAUUCUGUUUAUCUUUCCUUUUAUGAGCAGUAAAGGGGCUGGUUUAACUUAAAAGGUUAGCUUAGUAAGCCUAAAUAGUAUUUUAUAUAUGACUUUUCUGGCAAAUCUAAUUGAGACACUGGCCAGUCCAACUGGACCAGGAACCCAGCUUAGGGAAAUAACUUAUUAAUUAAAAAGCAUGCUAAAUUAGCUUGCUAGUCACUGGAGGAAAGGAGUUCUUAAUUAAAAUGAACACGGCCAUUAAAUUUGAAUUCCAUAUUUCCCAUUAGCAGCAGCGGAUUCCAGGAUGACGGAGGCCUGGGACGGCCCAAAAGGGAACGUCGGAGCCAAAGCAUUUAACUGAAAAGGCAUCAGGGACAGCAUGUUAAAGGCAUGAUUUAAAGUUACAAUUUGACUUCAGUUUUGAGCCCCGUUAUGCUGCCUGUACAACCUGUAUUGUUCCAUAGCCUCUUUCAUCUUCUGUCACCCACAUAACUUGCGGUGUUUGUUGUUUUACUUGUUCCUUCUUCCCCAUGCUAGAAUGUAAACUCCACAAUGGCAGGAUGUCUUUUAAUCUGGUUUUUUUUUUUCUUUUUUCUUUCUUUUUUUUUUUCUGUUGUCAUUAAAGCAUCACCAAGCACUUAGAAGAGUGCCUGGCAGACUCAAUGAGCAGAUAAAAUGUUAUUAAGUUCAAUGACUGAAUGACUGGGCCAGCAAUGAUACUUACCUGUGGUUCAUUCAUCACUGGUUCCUUAGGAAUAAAAUUGUUGAGCAAUGCACUAA